AGAGCUCUAGAGAGUGGUGCCGCCUUCCAACCUUCUUCCCCAAGCCCUGGUGGCCGGCUCCGCCUCUUCUCGAAUCUUUUCCACAGCCCAAAAUGGCCGCAGAGGUGUAUUUUGGCGAUCUAGAGCUCUUCGAGCCGUUCGACCACCCAGAGGAGUCGAUUCCGAAGCCCGUUCACACUCGCUUCAAGGACGACGACGGCGACGAGGAGGACGAAAAUGGGGUCGGCGACGCGGAGCUACGGGAGCGGCUUCGGCAGUGCGAGGAGACCAUCGAGCAGCUCCGCGCCGAGAAUAUCCUUUCCUCUCGCUGGGCCCUGUCACCCGGGUGUGGGGCCGGGGCAGCGCCAGGCGUGGGGCCGGGGCAGCGCCGGGCGAGGGCGAGGGCGCGGGCGGAAGUUCCAGGAGGGCCAGAAUUCCAAGUGCUUUCUGUCACCCGCCGGCGGACCGAGAGUCUAGGGUUCGGGGCGCGCAGGCUGCCUCGGCGCAGACCUCUUCCCCUCAGGGAGGCCGUCUCCUGACCAGACCCACUCCUGCCUCCCACCCGGGUGCCGUGUUUAGGGUUAUUUUAGGCUGCUCACCUGACAGAUUGUACACAAGCCCUUAAUUGCCCCCCUCUGUUUGAGGUCGUGGUGAGGUUUCAUAUUUCGCAGCCACGCUCAAAUUGUGCCGUCAUGUUACAGUUGUAGGUGAUGAAAUACCGGCUGCUUAGACGCGGGAUCGGUUUUUAUACCGGGGCAAACGCUAGUGGUCCCAGAAUGCAGAGUUGGGGGCCUCAAGGAAUCCGGGUGUGCUGAGAUAAUUGGUUAAUUGCUUGAUUAAAAUUGGGGAUUAAUUUUAGAGUUCUUCCACUCGGAGCUCGCUUCUGUGCUGAAGAUGCUUUGCAACGCCUUGAGGAAAACGCGCCAAAGAAGUUUCUGUUAGACUUGAGUUACAAGAUUGCAGAUUUUUCUUGAUUUGCUAUGGAAUAUUGGUGAACGAUACUAAGUUAGAUGGACCUAUAUUACAGAUUCUAUUCAUGAACAAUGCUAUUUCAAAGCAAUAUCAUCAAGAAAUAGAGGAAUUUGUAUCAAAUUUAGUAAAAAGAUUUGAGGAACAGCAGAAAAAUGAUGUGGAAAAGACUUCCUUUAAUCUUUUGCCCCAGCCAUCCAGUAUUGUGCUAGAGGAGGACCACAAAGUGGAAGAGUCCUGUGCCAUUAAAAACAACAAGGAAGCUUUCAGUGUUGUAGGAAGUGUCCUGUAUUUUACUAAUUUUUGCCUUGAUAAAUUGGGGCAACCGCUUCUAAAUGAAAACCCUCAGCUUUCCGAAGGAUGGGAAAUACCCAAGUACCAUCAAGUCUUCAGCCACAUUGUUUCUCUAGAAGGGCAAGAAAUACAAGUAAAGGCAAAAAGGCCAAAGCCUCACUGUUUCAAUUGUGGUUCUGAAGAACACCAAAUGAAAGAUUGCCCAAUGCCUCGGAAUGCUGCUCGAAUAAGUGAAAAGAGAAAAGAGUAUAUGGAUGCCUGUGGAGAAGCAAACAAUCAGAAUUUCCAGCAGCGAUACCACGCAGAAGAAGUAGAAGAAAGAUUUGGAAGAUUCAAGCCAGGAGUUAUUAGUGAGGAACUUCAAGAUGCACUAGGUGUGACAGACAAGAGUCUUCCACCUUUUAUCUAUCGGAUGCGCCAGCUAGGGUACCCACCAGGGUGGCUCAAAGAGGCUGAAUUGGAGAAUUCGGGGCUUGCACUCUAUGAUGGAAAAGAUGGCACUGAUGGGGAAACAGAAGUUGGAGAAAUACAACAGAAUAAAAGUGUCACUUACGAUCUCUCAAAAUUGGUCAACUAUCCUGGUUUUAAUAUAUCUACUCCCAGAGGAAUUCCAGACGAAUGGAGGAUCUUUGGUUCCAUACCAAUGCAGGCAUGUCAGCAGAAGGAUGUGUUUGCCAAUUACCUUACUUCUAACUUCCAAGCGCCAGGUGUGAAGUCUGGCAACAAGAGGUCUUCAUCUCACUCUAGCCCAGGUAGUCCAAAGAAGCAGAAGAAUGAAAGCAACUCAGCGGGAUCUCCCGCCGACAUGGAGCUCGAUUCAGAUAUGGAGGUACCACAUGGUUCUCAGAGCAGCGAAAGUUUUCAGUUUCAACCACCAUUACCUCCUGACACUCCUCCACUCCCCCGGGGAACUCCUCCACCCGUCUUCACCCCUCCACUCCCAAAGGGCACCCCGCCGCUGACUCCCAGUGACUCACCCCAGACCAGAACAGCAUCUGGAGCUGUGGAUGAGGACGCACUGACUCUAGAAGAACUUGAAGAACAGCAGAGGCGGAUCUGGGCAGCUCUUGAGCAGGCCGAGAGCGUAAACAGCGACUCCGACGUUCCUGUGGACACACCUUUAACUGGCAAUUCCGUUGCCUCAUCACCUUGUCCAAAUGAGCUAGACCUCCCUGUCCCGGAGGGAAAAACAUCUGAAAAGCAGACGCUGGAUGAGCCUGAGGUACCAGAGAUUUUUACAAAGAAAUCAGAAGCUGGACAUGCCUCCAGUCCAGACUCUGAGGUGACAUCACUUUGUCAGAAGGAAAAAGCAGAGUUGGCUCCGGUAAACACUGAAGGUGCCCUUCUUGAUAAUGGCAGUGUCGUACCAAACUGUGACAUCAGCAAUGGGGGCAGCCAGAAGCUCUUUCCUGCAGACACCAGUCCUUCAACGGCCACUAAAAUUCAUAGCCCUAUACCUGACAUGAGCAAAUUUGCAACUGGAAUCACGCCAUUUGAAUUUGAGAAUAUGGCAGAAUCUACUGGAAUGUACCUCAGGAUAAGAAGCUUGUUAAAGAACUCACCCCGAAACCAGCAGAAAAACAAAAAGGCCUCUGAAUAAUGGCUUGACUUAGCACUGAGAGCUAUUUAAUAACUUUGUUCCGUUAAUUAGUACUAAUUAAGUGGAUAGAUAGAAUGGUUUUCCUGUUUGUCCCUCCCAUGUUUAAAAAUCUAUCCAAGGUUCAUGUUCCAAAGUCAAGCCUAUUUUAAAGAAAGACUGAGCUCACUAGUUCAGUAUAUUUUAUUCUCACUGACAAAACUUGGGGGGAGAUGUGAAUAUGACCUGGUUUAGAGAGGGUUUGUUAAGGUUUAUACUAUUUUUGGAUUGUGACUAUCCGUCGAGAGUGAUGGUUUUUAUCUGUCUUUUGUACAUUGUUUUCCCUUUCUACAUUUUGCUAAUUAUCCUGUAUAUAAGUUUAAUAUAUCACUUUUUAAAAGAAAAAAUUCUACCAUUUUAAAUUCAUGUUUCAACUCCUACAACCAAAUGAGAAAAAUCAGGGAUGAGCAGCUUUAUCCCAUUUGGGGUAUUUUUGUAAGUGAUUUACAUGUGUCAAUUUUAGUAAUACUUUUACUUUUUUGUAACUUCAUCCUUCAUAUAUGCUUGCUAUACAGGUAUGUUCAUCUUUGUGUACAGAGGUUUAAUAAAUUAGUUUUCAUAUACAUAAUCUAAGACUUUGAAUACAAAAAAGUGAUUCACAGGUAAAAUCAGUGUAUAUAACCUUUUUUUUUUUUGAGACAAGGGUUUCACUCUUGUUGCCCAGGCUGGAGUGCAAUGGCACAAUCUCGGCUCACCGCAACCUCCGCCUCCCGAGUUUAAGCGAUUCUCCUGCCUCAGCCUCCGGAGUAGCUGGGAUUACAGGCAUGUGCCACCACGCCCAGCUAACUUCGUAUUUUUAGUAGAGAUGGGGUUUCUCCACGUCGGGUCAGGCUGGUCUUGACCUCCUGACUUCAGGUGAUCUGCCCGCCCAGCCUCCCAAAGUGCUGGGAUUACAGGCGUAAGCCACCUCACCUGGCCGGUGCAUAUAACUUUUAAGUUUAAAAGUAAAUUGUUGGCCAGGCGUGGUGGCUCAUGCUUAUAAUCCUAGCACUUUGGGAGGCCAAGGAGGAAGGAUCACCUGAGGUCAGGAGUUCGAGACCAGCCUGGCCAACAUGGCAAAACCCCAUCUCUACAUAAAUACAAAAAUUAGCCAGGUGUGGUGGUACAUGCCUGUAAUCCCAGCUACUCGGGAGGCUGAGGCAGGAGAAUCACUUGAACCUGGGAGUGGGAGGUUGCAGUGAGCCGAGGUCGCGCCAUUGCACUCCAGCCUGGGCAACAAGAGCAAAACUCCAUCUCAAAAAAAAAAAAAAAAAAAGGUAAAUUGUAAAAAUCAGUGGUAGCAAAACAAAAAUAAUGAUAGGAAUUGCAAGUUUGGGUGUUUUCAGUGGAUUUCAGCCUUAAAUAUAGAAACAGCAGAAUUUUUGAAAAGUAAUUAUUUUGAAAAAUGAAUGGCAUGCAGCUAGCCUUUGUAUAAAAAUAAUUUUCUAGAUUUGAACCCUAAUAGUUAAAAAUUAAAAAUUAAACAUAAACAUACUGCUUUUAAUUGUCAGGUAUAUAUAUAAGAUAGAGCUGAAACUGUGGUUUAGGUCUUUCUGUGGAAUGCCAUUACAUCUUUAUAUUAGUCAAGUCCAUGAAAAUAAAUGUUUAGAUCGUCUUGAAUUGUUAGUCUCAGGCAGUGUUAUCCUGCUCUCAGGCCAACAGGGGGAGCAAAAUAGAAACAUUCCAGAUAUAGCUUUCAUUUUUGAGAACUUGAGUAAUCAGAAUUUACUGUUCUGUAAAGAAUAAAGGAAAGGAAAAUUAUAAAGAGAGAAAUUUCUUUUUAAAGCCCUCACAGAAUGUGCUAGAAAUAGAAUAAAAUUUAAAAUACUUUUGGCUUCUUUUCCUCAGCUUAAGUUCAAAAUAAAAGCAAUCCUUUACAGUU